AGCUCUACGGCGGCCGCGCGCUCCAGGCCGGUCGCUCCACCCCCCGGCUCCCGGGACUGUGGACUCCACGACCCUGUCCUCGGCCCUGUCCGCGCCGAAGCAGCCCGGGACUGCGCAGCGCCCCGCGUGCCGAUCUUUUCCUAAUUCAGCAGCGAUUUAACCAAGAGCCUGGAAUAUUUUAAGGAGUAAUAAGAGACAUUUACAAACUAUUCUCUCUGAAGCCUGCUACCUGGAGGCAUCAUCUAGAUAAUCAGAACCUUGGCUUCCACAUCCUCCUCCCUUGUCUUAACUACAAACAUUUCUUUCUGCUGACUUCAACUCCUCAGACAUGGGAAAGUCUCUUUCUCAUUUGCCUUUGCAUUCAAGCAAAGAAGAUGCUUAUGAUGGAGUCACAUCUGAAAACAUGAGGAAUGGACUGGUUAAUAGUGAAGUCCAUAAUGAAGAUGGAAGAAAUGGAGAUGUCUCUCAGUUUCCAUAUGUGGAAUUUACAGGAAGAGAUAGUGUCACCUGCCCUACUUGUCAGGGAACAGGAAGAAUUCCUAGGGGGCAAGAAAACCAACUGGUGGCAUUGAUUCCAUAUAGUGAUCAGAGAUUAAGGCCAAGAAGAACAAAGCUGUAUGUGAUGGCUUCUGUGUUUGUCUGUCUACUCCUUUCUGGAUUGGCUGUGUUUUUCCUUUUCCCUCGCUCUAUCGACGUGAAAUACAUUGGUGUAAAAUCAGCCUAUGUCAGUUAUGAUGUUCAGAAGCGUACAAUUUAUUUAAAUAUCACAAACACACUAAAUAUAACAAACAAUAACUAUUACUCUGUCGAAGUUGAAAACAUCACUGCCCAAGUUCAAUUUUCAAAAACAGUUAUUGGAAAGGCACGCUUAAACAACAUAACCAUUAUUGGUCCACUUGAUAUGAAACAAAUUGAUUACACAGUACCUACCGUUAUAGCAGAGGAAAUGAGUUAUAUGUAUGAUUUCUGUACUCUGAUAUCCAUCAAAGUGCAUAACAUAGUACUCAUGAUGCAAGUUACUGUGACAACAACAUACUUUGGCCACUCUGAACAGAUAUCCCAGGAGAGGUAUCAGUAUGUCGACUGUGGAAGAAACACAACUUAUCAGUUGGGGCAGUCUGAAUAUUUAAAUGUACUUCAGCCACAACAGUAAAAACUGGAAGAGAUGGAUUUAAAGAAGAAAUAUCUAUUGAUAUUUCCUAUACUCUCAAUGAAGAGGUAUUUCCUAAUAGGAGACCUUAAAUUGAACAAACCUAAAGUUUACACUUCUAAGAGUACAGUUAAAAGUAUGUGGACCUGCAGUUCUUGUAACUCUCCACUCUGUGUUAAUGAUAUAUUUGUACUAGGAUCUUUUACUUGAAUCUAAAUUUACUGGUUGAUUUCCUUCUCCAGCCUAUCCCCUACAGGGAAAAGCUGAUACUUCCCCUAUAGUACAAUAAAUAAUUAUUUAAAAGUCAUAGCUCCAGUCACUACUGAAAACAUAAUUUUGGUGAUAAACAUAAUUUGAGAAACUUAAUUUCUGAAUGUUUUUAUAGAAAAUUACUGAAAGUCUAUUACUCAUGGAAGACUUUUAAAGAAUAACCUUUUUUCCUGUUUUAUAAAUUCCCAUUGUUAUAUGGUAGUAUUUCAGCUACACAAUAUUUUAGCUUUUAGCUAGACAUUUAUAGCUUUUCAUUUGUUGAAAUGGUAAUCAUCUGCAUGUUUUUGUCACUUAUUUCAGGUUAGUGAUUGCCUAACACUUAUAAGCCAAAAUAAUCUUUGCAAAAUUCCAUACCUAAAAUUUUGAAAGCCCCUAAUGUUUUCACACAUCUUUCUGUAUUAGUUAUAGUUUUGUGAAAUCUUUGUGUGAUCUUCAAACAUUAUCAUUUAAUGUACAAUACUGUAAAUAAACUGUGCAUGGCUUUUAUACAGCUUUAGUAAAUGUCAAAUAAAGUGGUACAGACUCAUUACAACAAGUUUCUCAUAAAAAUACAAUAAAUAGGAAAAUGAAAUUCAGAAACCCAUAGACUGGGAAUAGGUUCCAGUUACAGCUUGGAUCUGGCAUAAAAUAAAUUUGAAAUAAAAUAUUUUGAUGCUCCAUUUUUUUAUGUUGCUUUUCAUACUAAAGAAUGGUGUAGACAUGUUUUGCAACUGUUAGGUACCCAGUUAUCAAUUUUAUCAAUGUUUUAGAGGAGGAAAUUAUUUUUUUGGUAGAAAUUGUUCAAGAAAUCCUUAAUUGAAUGUCAUUAAAUGAUGGUGGCCAAAAUAAAACCUAUUUAGAAAUUUAAUCACUUUGCACAUCACUUGGAAUAUGAUGCCUCUAGUAGUUACUUUUUUAUAGUUUUCUACUUUUGGUUUUAUUUAAAAUUGUUUUCAAAUAUAGAUUAUUGACUUAUUCAACUUUGCUGUUUUAUAUUUUCAGUAUCAUUUUUCAUUUUUUUUUUUUUUUGUCUUUUCACUUACCAAGUUCUAGGGACAUUUAAAAUAUGUACUAAGUGUAGGAGUGGUUAUGAUACCAAAAAAUGUAGCUGGGUUGAGAUUAAUUUCGUUCUGUUUUCUCAUGACAGAAAUCAGGUUUCCCUUUCCCCACCCCUAAGUGCCUAACUUAGGUCUGAAACAGCCUGUUUAUUAGUCUGACUCUCUCAACCAUAAAACAUAAGCUUUAUUUAAUUCUGCCUUUAAACACACUCAGGUUUCCCCUUAAUUUUCAUAUUAUUUUCUGCAAGUUUUCUUGAGUAUCUUCAAUUCGUUGAAUGUGGUUUUUGGUUUUUUUUUGUUUUAACACUAGUCUUCCCUUAAUUCAUUGCUAACUCAAGCCAUCCUUACUAUUAAACCCAAAUCAGUCCUUUAAGUUCAUUAUGGCCUUUCUAGUAUUUAAAAAAAAAAAAAUCAUUUUCAUUUUUCUUCUGCUACGUUUCCUGACUACUACUGCAUACUUCUCUGAUACAGGUUCUGUUUGUAUUUUUUAUAUCAUUCUCAUUUUCUCAUUUGACAUGAUCUAUGUCUAUAUAUGAUAUAGGUCCCCUUUUGUCUCAAAAUUUUUAAUUAUGUGACUUCAAAAAUCACCUGUAUCUGUAGUAGGGCUUCCAAAUCUGCUUCUCCAUAUGUGACCAGUCACCUGUCUGCUUUCACAUUUAGCUAGUGAACUACACAUUUACUAAAAUGUGUAAAUUUUACACAUUUAGUGACUGUGUAAAAUAAAAAAAAAGUUAUUUUAUCAUAUCCUUUCUAUUAUGUUCCCAUCCUGUCCUCAUGUCCCAUUUACUUUAUUAUCACCAUUCAUUUCUUCAAAAUUAUCUUUUAGAUACGCUCAUACAAAAAUCAAUCCUUGUUUUCUUGCUUGUGUCUUUUAACCUUGGAAAAUUACAUCGUGUAAAUUAAACAGAUUUUUCUGAUGAUCUGUGCUUCUUAUAUACUAUUAGAGUGCAUGAUAGUAUCUCCUGAAAAGGAUGGAAAGUAGAAGCAUUUGCUUUUAGUCACUUAAUUUUGAAUCUUUUUUCUUCAUCUUUUGAAUUAAUUUUUUUUAUUAUAUCUACUUUUAGUGGAGUUUGAGUCAGAAAAAAACAAGAAUUUGAAACAAGUAAAAAGAUAGAAGAGAAAUAAAGAUGGUAUGUGACUACUUUCAGAGAGAGUUAAGUAACUGUCAGAAUAAGCCUGGAACAAAACAGGCUGUAAAUUAAUAAAACUACAAACACACAUUCAGGUGAAGCAGAAGUAUAGCCAUAAAACAUCUAGAAAGAGUGAAUGAGGCUUUUAGCUUUUCUUAGGUCAAUGUCCAGUGUGCUUUUUUCCAUGGGAAUAGGAUAGGUAUUAAUACGCUUUUCUAAACUGCUCUCAGACCUUAUCCAGAGGACAUGGUAAAGAUAUGUUACAGAAAUUUUUCUGAUACUUCCUGGAAUAACUUUAAGUUACACCCUAGUAGACUGGUCAUUCUAAUAAAAUCCAGUACUAUAACAAACCUCUGUAUGUUGAUAGCACAUUGGCCCUUUUUAGAGUUCUUUCCUAUGUUUUUCUUACGUGAUUUCCCACAGUUCCAUGAGUCCAACAAAGGAGAGUGAUAGGCUCCUUAUCUUUUAGAAGAGGAAGGAAAGGCAUGAAGAAGUUGAGGGACUGGCUGAAGAUCACGUACUUACUAAGUAGUACAACUGGAGCAAGAUCAAGUAUCUCUGUCUCCCAUAUCUGUGUUCUAUCAUUUAAAAUAUAUAUUGGAAAUCCCUGCUGACUCAGAUUGGUAUGAUUAAAAAUGAGAGGAAAGUUCAAAUAGUUAGUAGUGACAAACUAAUACUGCUGGACUAAGAUUUUGGUAGCAUUGUUUUCUAAAAUAUUUUAAAUGGAGAAUGAACACUUAUAAAAUGCUUUGGAACAUAAUCUUUAGCUUAAUUUUCUGUUAAAAUUUAGUACCCCUUCAUCAUUCCAAUAAAGAUAAGACUGAUCCAUUGUCUAAGGAAAUUAUUUAUAAAUAAUAGAGAUUAAUUUAUUUGAGAUUUGAAAUAAGAAUAGUAUGAAAAUAUUAGAUACCACAUAAAUUGUUUGAAAUUACUGAAUAACCAUCUUAAGUAUGGAACAUUUAAAUGGCUAUAUUUUAUUUGUGUACAGUUUUUCUGUGCCUUGUUAGGCCAGUGAAGCAAUUAUUUUCUCUAAGAAAAUGACAAUAAAAUAUAACACACUUCAGAUUGUCUGAUUUACAGUUUGGAAAGGACACCGCAAUGUUCAAAUAGGUAGGAGACCAUCAAAAACACAAUUAAAGUAACAUAUUAGGAGACUUGAAACUUCAGCCUAAUAAAUCCUUCAUGGUUCUUAGCCUUAUUAUUGUGAUAUAAUUCUAGAUAUUUUCUUGGAGGGCAUGUGCCCAACUCUCCCGCACCCCAUUUUGUUUGUCUUUUAAAGUUCUUAGAAUAAACAGUUCUUUAUAUAAUAAUUAUAUUUUAUUUAAGAAAAUAGUUUGUUAGGUACUUUUUAAAAGAUGUAAAUUUUUAAAUUUACAAAUACAUAUGGGUCUUUGAUAAGCAAUAGGAAUUGAAUUACAAGUUACUAGGGUUAUAAGCAAAAGGUUGCUUACCAUAAUGUCAUUAGGUCACGAUUUUUAGCUCACAUCUGGAAGCAGCAACUACUUGGCUCAAGUACAUAUAAGAGUAAUUAGUUUUAUUCUCUCUUUUUUAUAAAAUCGGGUUUCAGAUGAGAUGUUUAUCUUAGACUAUUUUAGGGAAAAAUUUUACAUGUUUGAGAUGGUGGAGUAAAAAGACUGUUAAACAUUUCUUUUAAAAAAUUAUUUUUACAUUACAACAAUAUAUUUAUGAUGUGUUCAGAUCAAAAAUUUAACUUCUGUGUCCCAGAUCUACUUUCAAAGUGAGAUUUUCACUUGUCAGCUUAAAUUUCUGACUAGAACUAACAUUUGUGUAUUUUUGUGCUUAGUCGGAAUACAAAUUUCACAGUGGAUUUUUGAAGUUUGUCCUUAAAUUGGAUAAAAUCAAGUGAUUAAAGUUACUAAAGAGAUAAAAAUGGUAAUUUCCAUUUUUAAAAGUAAUUUGGUUGUGUUUAUAGUUAUUUGUACAAGUAUUUAUCACAGACUCUAAAUUGAAAAAUGUAGUAUGAUCUAUAUUUGACCCUAAAAAUGUUGGAUUAAUUUAACAAAUAUGGCAGAUUUUUCAUAACUAAGUCUUAAGUCUUCUAAAAGGAAGCUGUUACCCUUCUGUUUUUAAUUACAUUAAUUGAAAUGUGUUUUAAGAGAUACAAUUUCAGCAUAUUUUAUAUAUUAAAAAACAAAAAAGGAUUAGUAUUGAGCCAGUGGCCAAAAGGUAAUAUUACUACCAUGUAGACUGUUAUAGUUCAAAUUGUCCCACUUCACCCAGAAUUUUAGAAACUAGAAGUCUGGGAGGUACUAUAUCAGCUGUAGUUGGGUAAUUCCAAGUGCUGAUAGUACUAUUCAUCUUUUUUAUUAUUGUGUCAGAUGAAACAAAUGCCAAGUUGCAAAAUAUGCAGAUUUUUAUUAUAUAAUGGUUUUAGGCAUAAAUUAUUAACAAGCCAUGCCUUAUGUGUUUCAUCUUAUAUUUUUCUUUAGAACUAAACUAUAACAGAUUUUGGAAAAUGAUUUGACGUGCUUGCUCACUUGAUUGACUUGGUCAGAUAUUUGAAUGAUGGUAUUACCUAGAUUCUAAUCCUUGAUUCUAGUUAUAUAAUAAAUAAUAUAGAAUAUGAAAAUAUGUUUGGGCAUUUACUGUUUAUAUUAUGUAGUAGCCUCCAUCAUGACACACUUACUACAUUUAUGAAUUGAGCAGUUCUGUAAUUGUAAUUAUUAUUGCUGUUCAUGUAACAAAACAUGCUUAUAAUAGCAAACAAAUAGAAAUGCCCCCAAAAUGCUAUUUUUUUAAUUCAGUUAUAACUGUUACUCUUGUAGUUGUGUAUGACGCAAUAAAAUUUGUAAAAAAAUUUCAGCAUGAAAAAUAAAAUUUGUAUCACUUAUGUAUUUUGGCUAUGCUUUUGAAAUUUCCUUAACAUAAACAAAUCAGUGUAGAUAUUCAAAAUCUUUUACCUUUAAUCCUUUUCAUCCUUAUAGUCCUUACCUGAACUCUACUUUAGCAUUAUCUUUGAUUUCUUUUUUUCAUUCACUUAACUUCCAAUCAGUACUCAAGCUUUAUCCAUUCUACCUCUGUAAUGUCUCUGGAAUUUAUCUCAUACGUGAAAUUUCCCUUGAUAUUAUAGACAUACCUUGGAUAUAUUGCAGGUUUGGUUCCACACCAUAUCGAUAAAGUGAUAUAAUCAAGCAAGUUACACACCUUUUUUUGGUUUCCCAGUGCAUAUGAAAGUUAUGUUUACAUCAUACUGUAGUCUAUUAAGUGUGCAAUAGCAUUAUGUCGAAAAACACAAUAUAUAUGCCUUAAUAAAAAAUAGGCUGUGUGCAGUGGCUCACACCUGUAAUCCCAGCACUUUCGGAGGCCAAGGUGGGAGGAUCACCUGAGCCCAGAAGUUCAAGACCAAAUUGGUCAACAUGGCGAGACCCCAUAUAAAAUAUAUACAUACACACACACACACACACACACACACACACACACACACACUAUUGCUAAAAAAUGUUAACGAUCAUCUGAAUGUUCAGAAGUUUAUACUCCUUUUGCCGGCACAGGAUCUUGUCUGGAUGUUGUUUGCUGAUAGAUCCAUGUAGUGGUUACUAAAGUUGGGGUGGCUAUGGCAAUUUCUUAAGACAACAAUGAAGUUUAUCACAUCUAUUGCCUUGUCCUUUCAUGAAAGAUGUCUCUAGCAUGUGAUGCUGUUUUGAUAGCAUUUUACCAAUGGUAGGUCUUUUUUCAAAAUUGGAGCCAGUCCUCUCAAACCCUGCCUCUGCUUUAUCGACCAUGUUUAAAUAAUUUUCUAAAUUCUUUAUUGUCAUUUCAGCAGUGGUCUCAGCAUCUUCACCAGGAGUAGAUUCCAACUCAAGAAACCACUUUCUUAGCUCAUUCAUAAGAAACAAUUCCUCAUCUGUUCAAGUUUUGGCAUCAAGUUGUAGCAAUUCAGUCACAUCUACAGACUCCAUUGCUAAAUUUUAGUUCUCUUGCUAUUUCCACAUCUGCUGUGACUUCCUUCACUGAAGUCAUGAACCCCUCAAAAUUAUCCAUGAGAGUUGAAAUCAAUUUCUUUCAAACUCCUGUUAAUGUUCAUAUUUAGACCUCUUCCCCUGAAUCACAAAUGUUGUUAAUGGCAUCUAGAAUGGCAAAUCCUUUCUGGAAGGUUUCAAUUUACUUUGCCCAGAUCCAUCAGAGGAAUCACUACCUAUGACAGCUAUGGUCUUACAAAAUGUAUUUCUUAUAUAGUAAGAUUCAAAAGUCAAAUUUACUCCCUGAUCCAUGGCUGCAGAAUGCACGUUGUGUUAAGAGGCAUGAAAACAACAUUAAUCUAUUUGUACAUCAUCAGAGCUGUUGGGUGACCAGGUACAUUGUCAAUGAGUAGUAAUACUUUGAAAGGAAUUUUUUUUUCCAAGCAGGUCUCAACAAUGGGCUUAAAAUAUUCAGUGAACCGUGUUGUAAACAGAUGUCAUAUUAUCCAGACUGUUCCAUUUAUUGAACACAGGCAGAGUAGGUAAAAGUUUUAAGGGUCCUAGGAUUUUCAGGAUGGCAAAUGAGCAUUGGCUUCAACUUAAAGUCACCAGCUACAUUCACCACUAAAGAGAGUCAGCCUGUCCUUUAAAGCUUUAAAGGCAAGCAUUGACUUCUCUUUAGCUAUGAAAGUUUUAGAUGGCACCUUUUUGUAAAAGAAGGUUGUUUUAUCUACAUUGAAAAUAUAUUGUUCAUUGUAACCACUUUCAUCAAUGAUCUUAGCUAGAUAUUCUGGGUAACUUACUGCAGGUUCUCCAUCAGCACUUACUGCUUCACCUUGCACUUUUAUAUUAUGGAAACAACUUAUCUCCUUAAACAUCAUUAACCAACCUCUUGGUAGCUUCCAACUUUUCUUCAAUAGCUUCCUCAUCUCUCUCAGCCUUCAUAGAAUUGAAGCGUGUUAGGGCUUUGUUCAGGAUUAGGCUUUCACUUAAGGCAAUGUUGUGGCUGGUUUGAUCUAUUGAAACCACUAAAACAUUCCCAUAUCGGCAAUAAGGCUGUUUGAUUUUCUUAUCAUUCAUGUUUUCUGGAACACUUUUCAAUUACUUACAGUAAGGAAAUAGCACUUUUAAUUUCCUUCAAGAACUUUUCCUUUGCCUUCACAACUUGUGCAAGAGACCUAGCUUUCAGCCUAUCUUGACUUUCCAAGAUUGUCCUUGGUGAGAAAUGCUUGAUUACUAGGUGUAAUUAUUUCUAGCUUUUGAUUGAAAGUGAGAGAUAUGUGACUCUUCCUUUUACUUGAACAGUUAGAGGCUAUUGUAGGAUUAUUAAUUGGCCUAAUUUCAAUGUUAUUUUGUCUCAAGGAGAGAGGGAUGUGGGAACAGCUGGUUAGGAGAGCAGUCCGAACACACACUUUUUUUUAUUACUUUCACUGCCUUACAUGGGUAUGGUUCAUGCUGCCUCCAAAUACUUACAAAAACAUCAAAGAUCACUGAUUACAGAUCAUUAAAAUAGGUUUAAUAAUAAUGGAAACAUUUGAAAUAUUGCAAAAAUUACCAAAAUGCGACAGAGACAUGAAAUGAGAACAUGCUGUUGAAAAAAAUGGCACUCAUAGACUUGUUGGACACAGGAUUGAAAGAAACCAAUUCAUCAAAACCACAAUAUCUGCAAAACGCAAUAAGGUGAUGCACAAUAAAAGGAAGUAUAUCUGCACUUCCUUCUUUUUUACUGAAAAAGCCCAAGUUCUUACUCUGGUGUUGAGAACCUUUCAUUAGCUGGCUACAAUCUCAGUUCACAAUCAUUUCUUAUUGCCCUUCAACAAUGUCCUGACCAAAUCGAGUUCUUUCUCAUUGGGAACAGUUCAUUCCUUUAUCCCUUCGCUCAUUCUGUUCCUUUUUUCUUAGAAAAAUUAUUUGCCCAUGUUUUUUAUCCCCCAAUUCUAUCUUUUUCAAUGCCCACUUCGUGUCCAACCCCUCUCUACUUUCCCUCUAAACUUACUCAAACACUUGGUGAACUUUUUCUGAAUGUUUUUUCUGAAUGUUUACUUUUAAAGGAGUUGCCCAGUCACAAAGUUUGAGCCAAGUUUUUUUGUUUUAAACUUGUUUUAAACUUUUGUUUUCAUCAACUUUUUUCAAACAAUUUUUGUCAGCUUAGAGGUUGUGUUUUAAUUACUAUUUUUAAAAUCUUGUAUGAGGUAGUAUGAUUUGAAAUUAGAUGGAAUGUGCCCAAAAUUAUCUCUGUAGAAUAAUAUGGAAAAACGAAAAUGAAAAGAUGUAUUACCUGAAUGUGCUCCUCCUAGCCAGUUUCUCAAGGGAGAAGAAUCAUUAAUAAGUUUGUGAGGCUUUUUUUUUUUUUCUGGUAGAUUUCUGUUUCCUUGAUCAGUGGUUUUUCAGAAUUUUUUAAAGCUUGUGAAAUACUUAUUUGUAAAUAGCAUCUUAUGAGGAACCUUGAUAUGUGACAAAACAGAUGCUUUGAUUUGAGAGCAGAAGACCUGCAGCCCCUGACUGCUCACCUUUCCAGGGACCCCUGAACAUUGGCCUAGAGGGUAGUGUACAGUCACUUCUUCAGUGAUAACUUACUGAGUGUGAUUCAACAAAACUGCUUUGGUUUAUGGGUGAAACAUAAUUUAUAACUAGGCAAAUGUCAGCUUAAAUUUAUAUUUUCUAAAUAGCACUGAAAAUGACAAUAGACAAAUGUAAUUUCUGAUUUUUAAGAAAUGAUUUUCCAUUUUAACAUACAUUUUAAAUGUUUUGUCUUCAAAGGGAAUCCUUAAAAAUGAUAUAUUGGAAACCACUGAUUUCUUAUUUUCAUUUCAUGAAUUUCAGAUUCAUGAAUGGAAUAUAUUGAUAAUAGCAUUUUUUAAGUUGCCCCAAAAAGAUGAAAUACAAAUAAUUUUAAUCCCAAAUCUAUUUCAGACACCUAACUUUUUUUUUAUUUUUUAUACUUUAAGUUCUAGGAUACAUGUGCAGAACGUGCAGGUUUGUUACAUAGGUAUACACGUGCCAUGUUGGUUUGCUGCACCCAUCAACCCGUCAUCUACAUUAGAUAUUUCUACUAAUGCUAUCCCUCCCCUAGCCCCCUACCCCACAAAAGGCCCCAGUGUGUGAUGUUCCCCUCCCUGUGUCCAUCUGUUCUCAUUGUUCAACUCCCACUUAUGAGUGGCAACAUGUGCUGUUUGGUUUUCUGUUCCUGUGUGUGUUUGCUGAGAAUGAUGGUUUCCAGCUUCAUCCAUAUCCCUGAAAAGGACAUGAACUCAUCCUUUUUUAUGGCUGCAUAGUAUUCCAUGGUGUAUAUAUGCCACAUUUUCUUUAUCCAGUCUAUCAUUGAUGGACAUUUGGGUUGGUUCCAAGUCUUUACUAUUGUGAACAGUGCUGCAAUAAACAUAUGUGUGUAUGUGUCUUUACAGUAAAAUGAUUUAUAAUCUUUUGGGUAUACACCCAGUAAUGGGAUUGCUGGGUCAAAUGGUAUUUCUGGUUCUAGAUCCUUGAGGAAUCACCACACUGUCUUCCACAAUGGUUGCAAUUUACACUCCCACCAACAGUGUGUAAAAGCUUCCUAUUUCUCUACAUUCUCUCCAGCAUCUGUUGUUUCCUGACUUAAUGAUUGCCAUUCUAACUGGCGUGAGAUGGUUUCUCACUGUGGUUUUGAUUUGCAUUUCUGUAAUGACCCGUGAUGAUGAGCUUUUUUUCAUGUUUGUUGGCUGCAUAAAUGUCUUCUUUUGAGAAGUGUAAGGUACUUAAUUCUUAAAUUAAAAAAAAAUACCCGGCCGGGCACGGUGGCUCACGCCUGUAAUCCCAGCACUUUGGGAGGCCGAGGCGGGUGGAUCAUGAGGUCAAGAGAUCGAGACCAUCCUGGCUAACAAGGUGAAACCCCGUCUCUACUAAAAAUACAAAAAAUUAGCCGGGCGCGGUGGCGGGCGCCUGUAGUCCCAGCUACUCGGGAGGCUGAGGCAGGAGAAUGGCGUGAACCCGGGAAGCGGGGCUUGCAGCGAGCCGAGAUUGCGCCACUGCAGUCCGCAGUCCGGCCUGGGCGACAGAGCGAGACUCCGUCUCAAAAAAAAAAAAAAAAAAAAAAAAAAAAUACCCUUCUUUAACAAAAUCAAGUUUCAAGUUUUCUGCCUUGUUGAUAACUUGUUAACAUUUUUUUAUUUUAGAAUAAAUCUAAACAGAGACCACACUGAUAUCUGUAACAACCUAUGUAAAGUUAAGAUUAAGGUUAAAUCACAUUUUUCACAGAGAGUGUUUUACUGAAAUAUAAACUUUUAUGCAUCUGAUAUUAUCUAAUUGUGUCCUUACUGGGUAACUUGUGUAUUUUUCAAGUUAAAGGAUUUCCUAAAAAUGCUUAUUUGAAUAUUUAUGUCAUUUGUCACACAUACUUUCAAAACAUAACCUUCUUCAACGAGUAUCUUCUUUUCCUUCCUAAAAUACUGUUAAUAGCUGGCUAUUUUGUAAGCCUGUAUCUGGUUUAAAAAAAAGAAGUGAAUAUUUUCAAUACUUAUGAACCAUAGAAUUCUGUAUUCUUUUCAUAACUUUUAACUUUUCCAUAGGACCUAUCACUAUGUAAAAUAUUAUACAUAUCUACUGAUUUAUUUAUUGCCUAUGUACCUAUACUAGAACAUAGUAAACAUGAGAACAGGGAAUCUUGGUUAUUAAUUCCUGCAGGACUCAACUACUUAUCACUCAAACAUUUGUUCUUGAAAAGAACUUCGUAUAACAUCAUUAGAUUUUUACAGAAUCUUUAAAAAAGCUUUAAUAUUUUCAAGGUUUUUUAUUUAUAUAAAUAUUGUUACUUUACCACUAGUGAUUUCAAUAGUGGCAUUGUCACAUGAUUCAAGAAGAGGAGGCCAUUACAUUACUGUUGUAUUAAAAAGUCAGUUCAGGCUUAAUAUAUAUGACUACUAUAAGUCAACCUCACAUUUUAAUGUAUGAAGAAGAUUGUAUGAACGAUCACAUUAAUUCAUUUAAAUAGUAUGUAUUUUGAUACUAAUUUUUAAGAAGAAAUGUAUCAUUCUCAUGGAAAUAAAAGAUAAUUUGAAAAGCA